ACUCUCCCCAGGAGACCCAGACCUAGAACUACCCAGAGCAAGACCACAGCUGGUGAACAGUCCAGCCUGUCUCCAGUUGGACUAGCCACAAUUCAAGUGCUUGAAAACCACAUGUGGAGCAGACAAGAUGGAGACAAAUUCCUCUCUCCCCACGAACAUCUCUGGAGGGACACCUGCUGUAUCUGCUGGCUAUCUCUUCCUGGAUAUCAUCACUUAUCUGGUAUUUGCAGUCACCUUUGUCCUCGGGGUCCUGGGCAACGGGCUUGUGAUCUGGGUGGCUGGAUUCCGGAUGACACACACAGUCACCACCAUCAGUUACCUGAACCUGGCCGUGGCUGACUUCUGUUUCACCUCCACUUUGCCAUUCUUCAUGGUCAGGAAGGCCAUGGGAGGACAUUGGCCUUUCGGCUGGUUCCUGUGCAAAUUCGUCUUUACCAUAGUGGACAUCAACUUGUUCGGAAGUGUCUUCCUGAUCGCCCUCAUUGCUCUGGACCGCUGUGUUUGCGUCCUGCAUCCAGUCUGGACCCAGAACCACCGCACCGUGAGCCUGGCCAAGAAGGUGAUCAUUGGGCCCUGGGUGAUGGCUCUGCUCCUCACAUUGCCAGUUAUCAUUCGUGUGACUACAGUACCUGGUAAAACGGGGACAGUAGCCUGCACUUUUAACUUUUCGCCCUGGACCAACGACCCUAAAGAGAGGAUAAAUGUGGCCGUUGCCAUGUUGACGGUGAGAGGCAUCAUCCGGUUCAUCAUUGGCUUCAGCGCACCCAUGUCCAUCGUUGCUGUCAGUUAUGGGCUUAUUGCCACCAAGAUCCACAAGCAAGGCUUGAUUAAGUCCAGUCGUCCCUUACGGGUCCUCUCCUUUGUCGCAGCAGCCUUUUUUCUCUGCUGGUCCCCAUAUCAGGUGGUGGCCCUUAUAGCCACAGUCAGAAUCCGUGAGUUAUUGCAAGGCAUGUACAAAGAAAUUGGUAUUGCAGUGGAUGUGACAAGUGCCCUGGCCUUCUUCAACAGCUGCCUCAACCCCAUGCUCUAUGUCUUCAUGGGCCAGGACUUCCGGGAGAGGCUGAUCCACGCCCUUCCCGCCAGUCUGGAGAGGGCCCUGACCGAGGACUCAACCCAAACCAGUGACACAGCUACCAAUUCUACUUUACCUUCUGCAGAGGUGGAGUUACAGGCAAAGUGAGGAGGGAGCUGGGGGACACUUUCGAGCUCCCAGCUCCAGCUUCGUCUCACCUUGAGUUAGGCUGAGCCACAGGCAUUUCCUGCUUAUUUUAGGAUUACCCACUCAUCAGAAAAAAAAAAAAAAGCCUUUGUGUCCCCUGAUUUGGGGAGAAUAAACAGAUAUGAGUUUAUUAUUGACUUCUUUUUUGAUUUUGGACCUCAGCCUUGGGUGGUCAGGGUGGGAAAUGAUAGGAAGAAGCUGUCAUCUGCAUCCUAGUUUGCCUGAAAUGAACCCAAAUAAUACCCAUUAUUAUUAGUCCUGAAUUAUGAGUAGUGAAUGAUACCCAUCAUUCUGGCAUCAUGAUGAGUAGUGUCCACUUCCAUUCUGAAAAGUGCCCUGCUGUGAAAAAUAAAUUAUAUAGUCAUCCUAGGUAAAUGAAGGAGGAGGGAGAAGUGUGAAAGAGUAUGGCUUAAAUCAGACAAGAUAUACAAGAAGAUACUUUAUAUAGGGCAGGAGCGGUGGCUCAUGCCUGUAAUCCCAGCACUUUGGGAGGCCGAGGCAGGCGGAUCACCAGGGGUCAGGAAUUCGAGAACAGCCUGGCCAACAUGGUGAAACCCUGUCUCUACUAAAAAUACAAAAAUUAGCUGGGCGUAGUGGCAGGCUCCCGUAAUCCCAGCUACUCAGGAGACCGAGGCAGGAGAAUCGCUUGAACCUGGAAGGCGGAGGUUGUAGUGAGCCAAGAAAACGCCACUACACUCCAGCCUGGGUGACAGAGAGAGACUCCGGCUCAG